AUGCCCCAGAGGGCCGCCGCCCCGCGCACGCGGCUGUGCUCGGGUCCCGGCCGUCGAGCACAAGAGUGUAGCUGCACCCAGUGGCUGUCCCGCGCCCACCCCGGAGCUCCGAGAAGCUCUGGAACCAGAUCGUUACCACCCGUGCCUGGCUGUCCGGCCUACCCCACGCCCGCCCGGAUCUGGAGGCGAACCCGCCACCGCCGCGCCCUCCCCGUAUCCGGCUCCGCAGUGACACGCGCAGCCCUCGCCCCACCCCGGGCCACGUCUCCCGCUCCCAGUGCAGCCACUCUCCUCCGGCCGAACAAAGAGGCCCCGGGACGCCGCGGAGCCUGCCAUGCCCGGACGGGUCGCGCCAGACCAAAGGGCCAAGGGCGGAGGCGGCGGUCACAAAGCGGCUUUUGUGCCACCCACCCGGCCCGCUGCGGAAGCCGAAACUGCCCCCGGCCGCCGCAGAAGCCGGACCGCGCCGCCCCCGUCGCUCCGGGCUCGGGAGGGACUCAAAAGCCGGUGCCUCCGGCGGCCAACCGCCACCCCGCAGCCCCGAGGGGCCCGGCAUCUGCCUCCGCACAGCCGGCCGCAAUCGGCCGGCCACAGGGCCAUAACCCGCCCGCUCCCACCCGGGACCCACCGGAACCGCAACCCGGGGCAACCUGGAGGAGACGCCGGGCUCCGAACAAAGGCGACAGCGGGGAUGGGGGGCCGGUCGUGGAUUCCCAGCCCGAGAGGCGACGAUGCGACGGCUACUCACAGGAAUAUGUUUACUCAUUGAAGAUUGUGGCCUAAUCAUACAGCCGGUCCCGAGGCGGCGGCGACACAGGCGGUGGCGGUGGCUGCAGGGCAGGAGGCGGCGGUGGUCGUGGCGGAGCGGCGGUGGCGGCGAUGCAGGCGGCGGCGGGGGCACCAGACUCUACCAUGCAGUGAGCGGCUCGGAGCAGAGCGCGUAGCCGAGCCGGCCCGCAGCCGAAGGAGCCAAUACACGCGCCGAGGCGCCCUUGCGUCACAAGCCCUCCCCUUUAUAGCCGGCGCGACGUGCAACCCUCCAGCCACCAAUCGCGGCCUGGAACCGCGGGCCAGGAGCCGACAGGCGGGGGCGGAGGCCCGCCCCCUCCGGACGUCACUCCGCGGCGGCCGCCGCCGGUGUGAACCGGUUGAUGAAUGGCUAAGCGCCGAGUCGGAGCAUCCCCGGGGCGGGGGAGGGAAGGGGCUGCCGGGAGUGCUCCGGGAUGCAGGAAGCCUGAAGUUAAGAAGGGGUGGGAGCGAGAGAGAUUCCGAUUUAUCGACUGGAAGGAAUCAUGCUGCAAACCACGUUUCUCAUAAUUAAAACGGUCCAGGAGUGCACACAUGUCACAUGAGGAGACUCGAAGUUUGCCUGAAUCGUAAAAUGCAAUCCUUCUAGGGCUGGAACCGCGUCUCAGUGUCGAGCCUGCUUUCUACUGCCUUAACCACGGUCAUCUUUGCCAGUGGUUUACCUUGGCACCUGGGCCCCGAGUACCUUCGUCAUCAAAUAAUAUUUAUGUCGCAAGACCGCUGUACCCGGUGACUCAACACCUUGCAUGCCACGGCCUUAGGCUUGGUCAAGAUGAAUUCUUGUCCCUGGGGGCGCUUUCAAGCGGGGAGAAACUUACCUUCGCAAAACUUAAGGCUAUAGAAGAUGGGGAGAGUAUCUUUUGAUGCAGACGAAGCCCUAUGCUCCCUAUAUUCUUUUUUUGAUCACACCUCUCUAUACUACGUACGCGUGCAACUGCAGUUGGCUCAAUUGUGGCAUUUCGAAAUCACAUGCAUCCUUUGUACUGCUGCUCACUUGAUAUGUUGUCUCAGAUAAUGAAAGGUUAGGAAGUGCUUAAAGAAAGCGUUUUUAGAAAUUAAGAAUCCUCGGUUUUGUCAAGCACUGAUGUAAUUCUUUGCGUCAAAGCUAAAGCUCUUCUUUAUGUUCGUUUUCAGUCCUCUUUUACUGACUUCAUUAUUUAAGCCCCUAAGAAGUAAAGUCUUAUCGCAAUUCUGUGCCAUACAAGGGCACCUCUGUUAUUUAUAAUCUGAAAACCCUUUCUCCUCAGCUCUGGAGAAGGACCAAACAGGACCUUUACCUGCUUUUUAAGAACUCAGUUUUCCACUAACACUGAAGCCUUUUGUUUGUUAUUUUCACCGAGUAUGAGAUUGGAGAGGGCUUUAGGGAUCAAAUUUUGUCCUCUUUCAGUGCCCUGCAACAUCUUAGGAUUUAUUAGAACUUCUAUUUAGAGACUGGUUGUAUAGUUAUUCAACUUUCUUAACUCUGUAAGUAAAAUAAGAACUUUAAAAAAACAAAAACAAACAAAAUCCUGGGCCAGACUUUCAAAGGAACAAAAACUCUUCGUCAUUUGGAAGAAAAUGGCUCACCUACGACACAUUUUAAUCCAUUAAAAUCAAGGAAAACUAGCACACUUGAGAAAUAUGUCCCUUUACAAAUAAAUGAUUUAAAAAAGUAAAGACUUUAAAAUCUUAAAUUCUAAGAAAAUAUAGAAAGCUUAAAAAUCUUGGGUGGUAGGGGCAAAGCUAAGCAGGCUGGGGAACUCAUGUCGAAAAAAAGGGACAGAUUUCAUAUAUAAGAACUAAAAACUUUUAUAUGGCAAAAGGCUUUUGACAAAUGUCAAUUUCACACUGGGGGAAAUAUUGGUGAUACUUCAUGGGUAGGGUUAAUAUAAAAAGCUUGGCCAAUGUAUAUAAUAGUGUAGUUAAAAAGCACAUAUUCAGUCAGCCACUCUUACUCCACAAGUUGGUAAACACAGAUAAUUGGAAUAGUGAAACUUUUUCAUGUAAUGGCAUUUCAAAAAAUACAUUUGGUGGGACAAGAUAUAAACUCAGCAAAUGAUUAACAGAGCCAAAUAUGUGUUAGCCAAUUUUCUUGUAGAACUUGUGAUACAAGUUGUGAGCCUUGUGAUCCACAGAUCCUGUAAUUACCACAAGCAGUGCUGACACGAAGUAUCCAGUCAGCUAUGCUCAUCAAGUUCUAAAAGCUCUCAAAUUCUCAAGUGGCCUGGGGGUCUUAGCCUCUCAGACAAGGUACCAUCUUAUCCUACUAUGAAAGUAACAUAUUUAAAGGAUGAAAAAAUAAGGCUUUUGCUGUUGAGAGAAACGAUGCAUUUUAUUUUAUGUAUUUAUUUGAGAUGGAGUCUUGCUCUUUUGCCCAGGUUGGAGCACAGUGGUGCAAUCUUUGCUCACUGCAACCUCAGCCUCCUGGGUUCCAGCAAUUCUCCUGCCUCAGCCUCCCAAGUAGCUGGGAUUACAGCCACCUGCCACCACACCUGGCUAAUUUGUUUGUACUUUUAGAAAACUCCAUGUUGACUAGGCUAGUUUUGAACUCCUGACCUCAAGAGAUCUGCCUGCCUCAGUCUCCCAAAGGAAAGGACACAUUUUAAACAAGAUAUAAGUGUGGUCUUGCUGACCAAUCCAUUAAAUGUUCCUGCUUGUCAGCUGCCAUUGUGGUUCACUGCUAUGCUGAGGGUGUCUGCUGUAUUUAGUUUAAUACUUUUAAGCUGCAGAUUCUUGGAGAACAGUAGAACAUCCCAGCAUUGGUCAGGAGACUUCUGUGAUUUGAGGACUCACUAACCCUUACAGACUUGCACUCAGAGCAUUAGCACCUGUACUUAUUUAAAGUGGGUCUCUAACAGACUUGAAAAUAGUGCUUCCAGACAUCAAAAAGGGAGAAAACACCUCUAAAAGCCAAUGCUUACUCUAAGCUCCAGGAGAGGCUCUAAAAUAGAGGAUUUUCUCUCCUGCUAAACAAGAUUCUCAGCUGGAAGUUACUUCUCUCAGCAAAACAUGUGUCCUUAACCUCAUCACGAUAGGCAGGGCUUUCUAUUGACAAUUCAAAAUAUAAAAGCCAGCAGUUGGGAAAUAAGACUAGAAGAAUAUUAUAAGGAAGUUGAGCAUGGUGGCAUACAGGCUCAUGCCUGUAAUCCCAGUACUUUGGGAGACCAAGGUGGGUGGAUCACCUGAGAUUAGGAGUUAGGAGUUCAAGACCAGCCUGGUCAACAUGGUGAAACCCAUCUCUACUAAAAAUACAAAAAAUUAGCUGGGCAUGGUGGCAGGCACCUCUAAUCCCAGUUACUUGGGAGGCUGAAGAAGGAGAAUCACUGGAAAGCUGGGAGGCAGAGGCUGCAGUGAGCCGAGAUCAUGGCACUGCACUCUAGCCUGGGAGACAGAGUGAGACUUCAUUUCAAAAAAAGAAUAUUAUAAGCGAUAUUUUUAUGGAAGAGGAAAGACUGCAGAAGGCAAGAGUGCAGAGGAAGAUUGGCAAAUCUUGAUGAAGAAGAACAGAGAAAUCUUCACAAGAACAGCAGAUCUAGUAAACAUUGAUUCCAUUUUACCAAGUUUACAAAAGGAGUGAAGGAUUCCUUGAUUUUCAAUCUUCUCAGAUUGGUUGGGGCUACAAGGAAGUCUGAUAAAAACAUUUAACAUAGCAAGAGUAAUAUCAUUGCCAUAAUAGAUUAAACGUGACAAUAUCAACCUAGAAAAAGACACUAGAUUGCAAGGUAUAAUGACAGUCUAGCAAAUAUAUGUAAUAGAGGCAAAUACCCCAAUGGGCCAUAAUCUAGUAAGUGUCUGGAUACUAGUGCAGAGGGUAAGUUCCCAUACCCAUAUUUAACAAGAGUCCUAAAAAUUCAAGUAUGCCAUGGCUGCUGUCAGCAUUGUUAAAGUUUAUUUCCCUCUUGCUGUUUUAGAACAGCCUAUUUUAUAUCCAAUUAAUUUUCUUAUAUGAUUAUUAAAAAUAAAUAUGUAGUAUACAGGCAUACCUUCAUUUAUUGUGCUUUGCAAAUAUUGUUUUUUUUUUUUAACAAAAUGAUGGUUUGUGACAGCUUUUUGUCGAGCAAGUCUAUCAGAGCCAUUUUUCCAAUAGCAUGUGCUCAUUUCAUGUCUCUGUGUUACAUCUUGGUAAUUCUCCCAAUAUUUCAAACUUUUAAAUUAUUAUUGCAUUUGUUAUGGCAAUUUGUGAACAGUGAUCUUUGAUAUUGUUAUUGGAAUUGUUUUGGGCCACCACAAACUGUACCCAUUUAAGAUGGCAAACUUAUUUGAUAAAUGUUGAAUAUAUUCUGACUGCUCCGCUGAUGGGCCAGUCCCUCAGUGAGACACAGCAAUACUGAAAUUAGGCCAAUUAAUAACCCUACAGUGGCCUCUGAGUGUUCAAGUGAAAGGAAGAGUCAUUCAUCUCUCACUUUAAAUCAAAGCUAAAAAUGAUUAAGCUGAGUAAGGCAAGUUGAAAGCAGAGAUAGGCCGAAAACUAGGCCUCAUACCCAAAACAGUCAAGUUGUGAAUGCCAAGGAAAAGCUCUUGAAGGAAGUUAAAAGUGCCACUCCAGUGAACACAGGAAUGAUAAGAAAGUGAAACAGCCUCAUUGUUGAUAAGGAGAAAGUUUUAGAGUUCUGGAUAGAAAACCAGCCACAGCAUUCUCUUAAGUCAAAGCCUAAUUCAGAGCAAGGCCUUAACUCUCUUCAUUUUUAUGAAGGCUGAGAGAGGUGAGGAAGUUGUAGAAGAAAAGUCUGAAGAUAGCAGAGGUGGAUUCAUGAGGUUUAAGAGUAGAAGCCCUCUCCCUAACAUAAAAAUGAAAGGUGAAGCAGUAAGUGCUGAUGGAGAAGCUGCAGCAAGUUAUUGAGAAGAUUUAGCCAAGAACAUUGAUGAAGGUGGCUACACUAAAUAACAGAUUUUCAAUGUAGACAAAACAGUCUUAUACUGGAAGAAGAUGCUGUCCAAGACUUUCAUAGCUAUAGAAGUCAAUGCUUGGCUUCAAAGCUUCGAAGGACAGGCAGUUCUCUUGUUAGGGGCUGAUGUGGCUGGUGACUUUAAGUUGAAGCAGAUGUUCAUUUACCAUUCUGAAAAUCCUAGGACCCUUAAAAAUUAUGCUAAAUCUACUCUGCUGUGCUCUAUAAGUGGAAGAACAAAACCUGGUUGACAGCACAUCUGUUUAGCAUGGCUCACUAAAUAUUUUAAGUCCACUGUUGAGACCUACUGAUAAAACGUGAUUUAUUUAAAAAUACUAUUGCUCCUUGACAAUGCACAUGGUCACUGAAAUGCUCUGAUGGAGAUGUACAAGGAGAGUAAUAUUGUUUUCAUGCCUUCUAACACAGCAUCCAUUCUGCAACCCAUGGAUCAAGGAAUAAUUUUGACUUUCAGGUUUUAAUAUUUAACAAGUACAUUUCAUAAGGUUAUAAAUUGCUGUAGAUGGUGAUUCCUCUGAUGGAUCUAAGCAAAGUAAACCAAAAACAUUCUGGAAAGGAUUCUAGAUGCCAUUAAGAACAUUCAUGAGAGGAGGUAAAAGUAUCAGCAUGAACAGGAGUUUGAAAGAAGUUAACUCCAACUCUCAUGGAUGACCUUGAGGGCGUUCAAGACUUCAGUGGAGGAAAUCACUACAAAUAUGGUGAAAAUAGCAAGACAAUUGGAGUUAGAAACAGAGUCUGAAGAGUUGACUAAAUCGCUGCAAUUUUAUGAUCAAACUUGAAUGAAUGAGGAGUUGCUUCUUAUGAAGGAGAAAAGAGAGUGGUUUCUUGAGAUAGAAUCUACUGCUGGUGAAGAUGCCGUAAGCAUUGUUGAAAUGAUAAAGGAUUUAGAAUAUCACAUAAACUUAGCUGAUAAAGCAGUGGGUGAGUUUUAAGAGGACUGAUUGCAACUUUGAAAGGAGUUCUCUUGUGUGUAAAAUACUAUCAAACAGCACUGCCUGCUACAGAGAAAUUUUUUGUGGAGUCAUCAAUGCAGCAAACUCCAUUGUCUUAUUUCAAGAAAUUGCCACAGCCACCUUAACCUUCAGCAACUACCUCCCUGAUCAGUCAGCUGCCAUCAUCACUGAGGCAGGAUUCUCCAACAGCAAAGAUUAUGACUUGCUGAAGGCUCAGAUGACUGUUAGCAUUUUUUAGCAAAAGUAUUUUUAAAUUAAGGUAUUCUAGGGUACCCGUUUUCCCCACUUCCUUUCUGUGUCUUGACCAAAAUCACAGUGACCCAGCCAGCUGUAGCCAUAGGUUUUCCUCAGCUGGCUUGAACCCAAACCAGCUUGAACAUUCCCAGGCACUGAUAAUAAUGUCUUGGUUUACUGGAAAGAAACUGACCCCGACCCUGAGCCGAAUUCCUUAAAUUUUCAUGUAAACUCCAUCCCCUCACCCCCUGGCUACAGACUAAUGUGGGUAAAACAUCCCUUUUCUCUUGCUGUCCAUCACAAUAAUACAUUGCAACACCCUGCAAGUUCCUUUAAUAAAUGUUUUGGACUGAUCA